GAAACCCACGAGGGGACGCGGCCGAGGAGGGUCGCUGUCCACCCGGGGGCGUGGGAGUGAGGUACCAGAUUCAGCCCAUUUGGCCCCGACGCCUCUGUUCUCGGAAUCCGGGUGCUGCGGAUUGAGGUCCCGGUUCCUAACGGUGGGAUCGGUGUCCUCGGGAUGAGAUUUGGCGUUUCCUCGGGGCUUUGGUGGGAUCGGUGUCCUCAGGAUGAGAUUUAGGGUUUCCUCGGGGCUUUCGGGAUCUUCACCUAAUAUCCGGUAUUAUUUUAUGAGAGGAGUGGUCUUGGCUGUCAGAACUGGAUCCCUGGGGUGAUAUUUGGGAAUUAGUGGAGUGAUCUCUGAAGACCUAGGGCUAUGAUCUGGAGCUGCUGUGGCUGAAAUUUGGGGCCUCUGAAGUGGCAUGGAGAUUGAGGUCCAGAGAGCCUGAGAUCUUGAGGGCUGACAUUUGGAGAGAUGGGGUCGAGGGUUGUCUUUGGGCCUUGACUGCUUUGGGCCUUUCUCACUCUCAUUCCCGGGAUGCUUUGCCAGAAUCUCUGCUGGAUUGGCCGUAACCCUGUCCCCGAGCGGGCUCACAGGGUCUGAAGGCCACGCAUGAGGCAAAGGUAAAGUUCUGAGCCACCCGGUGCCUCCUUCCCAGGACUGCAAGAUGGAGGAAGGCGGGAACCUAGGAGGCCUGAUUAAGAUGGUCCAUCUACUGGUCUUGUCAGGUGCCUGGGGCAUGCAAAUGUGGGUGACCUUCGUCUCAGGCUUCCUGCUUUUCCGAAGCCUUCCCCGACAUACCUUCGGACUAGUGCAGAGCAAACUCUUCCCCUUCUACUUCCACAUCUCCAUGGGCUGUGCCUUCAUCAACCUCUGCAUCUUGGCUUCACAGCAUGCUUGGGCUCAGCUCACAUUCUGGGAGGCCAGCCAGCUUUACCUGCUGUUCCUGAGCCUUACGCUGGCCACUGUCAACGCCCGCUGGCUGGAACCCCGCACCACAGCUGCCAUGUGGGCCCUGCAAACCGUGGAGAAGGAGCGAGGCCUGGGUGGGGAGGUACCAGGCAGCCACCAGGGUCCCGAUCCCUACCGCCAGCUGCGAGAGAAGGACCCCAAGUACAGUGCUCUCCGCCAGAAUUUCUUCCGCUACCAUGGGCUGUCCUCUCUUUGCAAUCUGGGCUGCGUCCUGAGCAAUGGGCUCUGUCUCGCUGGCCUUGCCCUGGAAAUAAGGAGCCUCUAGCAUGGGCCCUGCAUGCUAAUAAAUGCUUCUUCAGAAA